AGACCCCUCCUGCGAGGCCAGGGGCUGUGGCCAUUGGGAGUUUGUCCCCACGGACCCCUCCUCCCCCAGAGGGCACGCCAGUCUUGAAGCAACAUGAGCAGCCCGGAGCCCCCCACAGAGCCCCCCGAGCCCGACAACCCCACCUGGUCGACUCAGCCCACGUAUAGCAACCUUGGUCAGAUCCGUGCCCACCUGCUGCCCUCCAAGGCCUGCCGCCUCCGGACCCCUGGGUCCCUCUCCACCAACCCAGAGCCCCUGCCCCCACCCCUGCCCAAGAAGAUCCUAACCCGGACCCAGUCACUGCCCACCCGCAGGACCCUCCAUCCCAGCUCCAUCCAAGUACAGCCGCCUCGGAGACCCUUUCUGGGGUCCCACAGUGUGGACAAGAGCCAGGCUGCAGUGGGACCAGCCUGUCUCCCUGCAGAGCUGACCUUUGGCCCGGCUGACGCCCCACUGGGCCUCUCCCUCCGCGAUCUGCACAGCCCGGAGGCUGUGCACACUGCACUGGCUGCGCGGCAGCUGCAGGGCCUCCGUACCAUCUAUGCCCGGCUCCGUGCCCGGCUCAUGGGGGGCCACCCCGGGCCCUGCCACCCCGGCCACAGCUUCCGCCUCCUAGACAGCUCACCCUGCGCAGAGAGCGGGGACGCCCUGUAUUACCGCGUGGUGCGCGCGCACGAGGACGCCUGGCACAUCCUGGUCGCCAAGGUGCCCAAGCCCGGGGCGGACGUGCCCCACCCGUGGGGCCUGGAGCUGCAGGCCUCCCUGUCUCCACACUUCAAUCUGCAGGGGCUGUGUGGCCUGGUGCCUGAAGGCACACUGCCCGGGGCGCCCUGGAGAGGCGCAGUGGCGCUGGCAGCCGAGGUUCCAGAGCGCACGGUGGCGCAGUGGCUGGCGGAGGCCUGCACGCAGCCGCCGGAGGAGUUCGUGUGGGCUGUGGCCCUGCUGCUGCUGCAGCUGAGCGCGGCCCUGAAGUUCCUGGAGGCGUGGGGCGCGGCCCUAGUCGAGUUGCGGCCGGAGAACUUGCUGCUGGUGGCACCUCGGGGCUGUGCGACGACGGGGCCCCCACGCCUGCUCCUCACUGACUUUGGCCGCGUCUGUCUGCAGCCCCCUGGACCCCCGGGAUCCCCGGGCCCCCACGCGCCGCAGCUGGGCAGCCUCCUCCGAGCGCUGCUCAGCCUUGCUGCGCCCUCGACCACGCCUUUGGCCGCGGGCCUGGAGCUCCUGGCAGCACAGCUGACCCGCUUGCGGCCCUCGGCGUCCCGGACGCGGGGCGCGCUGCAGGCGCUGCUCUGGGGGCCCGGGCCUGAGCUGCGCGGCCGCGGAGCACCGCUUGGUCCCUGGCUCCGAGCGCUCGGGCCCUGGCUGCGGGUGCGCCGCGGGCUGCUGGUCCUGCGCCUAGCAGAGCGGGCCGCAGGUGGGGAAGCUCCCAGCCUCGAGGACUGGCUGUGUUGCGAAUACCUGGCCGAGGCCACCGAGUCCUCGAUGGGCCAGGCCCUGGCGCUGCUGUGGGACUGACCCCAACCCAGGGCGAACACACCUGGUCCAGGCCUGCCCAGGAGGCAGGGCUGGGGCUGAGGUCAGCGUCUCCAUGAUAGCCAAGACACCCUCUUCCUGCAGAGUCCAGGAGCGCAGCAGAGAGAGCAAUGCCCCACUCCAGAGCCUCCCCUCCCGUGCUGGGGAUGUGGGUCAAGGGCUUCCCAGGAAUGCAGCUGCCCCUCCAGGGCUGGGGGCUGGCCAGCGCCUCCUGUGUUGGGCAGCAGCUCUCUGAAGCCAGGGCCCCCACGCCACUUCCAGGUGUGGACAACCCCGCUGAUCAAUGUCUCUCUGUGUUCUGCCUUCCCCAGCAGCCAGGGCGCUCUUCCGCGUGGGUUCUGUCAUUGUCUCCAUGAGAGGCCAAUGCCGGGACCAGAGGCAUUCCUGGCUCUGGAGCACCCCCUUGUGCUGAAGAUGGCCAGUGAUUUUGGGCAUGUGAAUGCCCCUGUCCCUGGUGGAGAAUUGCUUGGUGGUGUCACGGGAAGGGAAGGCUCCCUGGGACCUUAGACACCCAGCUCAUCUCAGCGGGGUCUGGACUCACCUUCCCUAAAACAGUCCCCGCGGUUCCCUGCCACCUCCCCUCAAUCCCUCUGCGCCCACCCUGCCUCCCUCCCUGUUCCUCCGUGACACACCAACUUCUUUCGCGCCCCCAAGCAUUUGUGUAGGCUGUUCCCUCUGCCAUACUGUUCCAGUUCCACUUUCUUUUUCUUUUUUUUUUUUUUUUUUUUUUGAGACGAUCUCGGCUUACUGCAAGCUCCGCCUCCCGGGUUCACGCCAUUCUCCUGCCUCAGCCUCCCGAGUAGCUGGGACUACAGGCGCCCGCCACCACGCCCGGCUAAUUUUUUGUAUUUUUAGUAGAGACGGGGUUUCUCCGUGUUAGCCAGGAUGGUCUCCAUCUCCUGACCUCGUGAUCCGUCCGCCUCGGCCUCCCAAAGUGCUGGGAUUACAGGCGUGAGCCACCGCGCCCGGCUACAGUUUCACUUUCUCUAAACAAAUAAAGGUGCCCACUCUGGGCCAUCGCUAGCUCCUUA